AAUAAAGGGGUCUGAGCCGGUCGCCUGAGCCUGAAAAGUGCUGUCACGUCAGCGGAAGGAGGCGUCCCAGAUCUUCUCAGCUGUCUUGGUGCCAGCCUUCCUAGUCUUCCUACCCACACUCCUACCUGCUGUCACAGGCCACAGCCAUCAUGCCUCGGGGUCACAAGAGUAAGCUCCGUACCUGUGAGAAACGCCAAGAGACCAAUGGUCAGCCACAGGGUCUCACGGGUCCCCAGGCCACUGCAGAGAAGCAGGAAGAGUCCCACUCUUCCUCAUCCUCUUCUCGCGCUUGUCUGGGUGAUUGUCGUAGGUCUUCUGAUGCCUCCAUUCCUCAGGAGUCUCAGGGAGUGUCACCCACUGGGUCUCCUGAUGCAGUUGUUUCAUAUUCAAAAUCCGAUGUGGCUGCCAACGGCCAAGAUGAGAAAAGUCCAAGCACCUCCCGUGAUGCCUCCGUUCCUCAGGAGUCUCAGGGAGCUUCACCCACUGGCUCUCCUGAUGCAGGUGUUUCAGGCUCAAAAUAUGAUGUGGCUGCCAACGGCCAAGAUGAGAAAAGUCCAAGCACUUCCCAUGAUGUCUCCGUUCCUCAGGAGUCUCAGGGAGCUUCACCCACUGGCUCGCCUGAUGCAGGUGUUUCAGGCUCAAAAUAUGAUGUGGCUGCCGAGGGUGAAGAUGAGGAAAGUGUAAGCGCCUCACAGAAAGCCAUCAUUUUUAAGCGCUUAAGCAAAGAUGCUGUAAAGAAGAAGGCGUGCACGUUGGCGCAAUUCCUGCAGAAGAAGUUUGAGAAGAAAGAGUCCAUUUUGAAGGCAGACAUGCUGAAGUGUGUCCGCAGAGAGUACAAGCCCUACUUCCCUCAGAUCCUCAACAGAACCUCCCAACAUUUGGUGGUGGCCUUUGGCGUUGAAUUGAAAGAAAUGGAUUCCAGCGGCGAGUCCUACACCCUUGUCAGCAAGCUAGGCCUCCCCAGUGAAGGAAUUCUGAGUGGUGAUAAUGCGCUGCCGAAGUCGGGUCUCCUGAUGUCGCUCCUGGUUGUGAUCUUCAUGAACGGCAACUGUGCCACUGAAGAGGAGGUCUGGGAGUUCCUGGGUCUGUUGGGGAUAUAUGAUGGGAUCCUGCAUUCAAUCUAUGGGGAUGCUCGGAAGAUCAUUACUGAAGAUUUGGUGCAAGAUAAGUACGUGGUUUACCGGCAGGUGUGCAACAGUGAUCCUCCAUGCUAUGAGUUCCUGUGGGGUCCACGAGCCUAUGCUGAAACCACCAAGAUGAGAGUCCUGCGUGUUUUGGCCGACAGCAGUAACACCAGUCCCGGUUUAUACCCACAUCUGUAUGAAGACGCUUUGAUAGAUGAGGUAGAGAGAGCAUUGAGACUGAGAGCUUAAGGCAGGGCUGGCACUAUUUCCUUGGCCAGGGUACCUUAUGGGGCCAUAUCCUACAGAUCCUCCCAUUUCUAGGGAGGUCUGAAGUAGAAUUUUCACUUUAUGUUAGAAGAGAGUAGUGAGCUUUCUAAGUAGUGCAGUAUAGUAGAGGCUGGAGGGAACAAGAUAUGUAUCUUUCUUUUGUUACACAUGAGUAACUUGCAGAUUUAUGUUUUAUCUCUGUCAGUUAUCAACAUUGUUCCUGUUAAGUGAAGGUUUAUUUUGCUUCAGAUUAUACAAUUAUCAAUAACAUAGCUCUCACAUUCAUGGCUGUUUAACCAAUCUGAAAGUUACGGUUUGGGAAUUAAUAAAACAAAGUCAUACAACACAUUUUCUUUGUAAUUGAGAACUAGAUAACAUGGUAACAGAGAAUUGAUUUUCAUAUGAAUCUUAACUCCACAGUAAAAUAGUUGACAUCAUAAUAUGAAGAGAAAGAAAAGGAAAAACAGAAAUGUAAAAGUUGUUUAAUUCUUGGUUUGCCUAAUUCGUUUUCCUAUUUCUUUUCAUACAAAUAAAGGAUACCUGGAUUUAUUUAGGUUA